AGUGAAAGACUAGGGAGAGGGAUGGCUAGUGAGGUUUAGAUCAUGUUGAGCCCUACCUUUGUUUUGUGGGAUGUUGGAUAUCCCUUAUACACCUAUGGAUCCAUCUGCAUUAUUGCAUUAAUUAUUUGGCAAGUGAAAAAGAGCUGCCAAAAAUUAAGCUUGGUACCUAACAGGAGCUGUUGCCGGUGUCACCGAAGAGUCCAACAAAAGUCUGGAGAUAGAACAUCAAGAGCUAGGAGAACUUCACAGGAAGAAGCCGAGAAGUUGUGGAAGCUGCUGUUUCUCAUGAAAAGCCAGGGCUGGCUUCCUCAGGAAGGAAGUGUGCGGCGAAUCCUGUGUGCAGACCCCUGCUGCCAAAUCUGCAAUGUUAUGGCUCUGGAGAUUAAGCAAUUGCUGGCAGGUGAGAACAACCAGAUCUCCCUGACUUCACUGGGGCCAUCACAGGGCUCCUCUUGCCUAGAGGCUUUGUCCACAUCUAGUGUGUCUUUUAAGCAUAGUCAGGAUCUGGGCUCCCCGAAAUCCAAAGAGCUUUCACUGGCAUCUGUAACUCCAACACUGUCACAAUUAAUGGAUCAGAAAUCUUUAACCCAGUCAGCUGCCCGGUCAGCUGGUGCAGACAGCGUCCAAGAUUCCUGGGCUGAUCACUUUCAGCGAGGACAGAGAUCUCAAGUCCCAGCUGUGUCCCAGGUCAUGGGAUCUCUGUCUUCAAACUUUGAGAAGCCUGGAAUUCCUCUGAGCCAGCAGGAGAGGACGAAAAACAACUCCAAAUUUGUCCUGGAGAACCAAGAAGCUCCAGAAGUUGGCUUGGAUAACAAGAUGAAGCUGUUUCUGCACUGGAUUAACCCUGAAAUGAAAGAUCGAAGGCAUGAGGAAUCCAUUCUCCUUUCUAAGGCUGAGACAGUGACCCAAGACAGGACAAAAAACAUUGAGAAGAGUCCAACUGUCACCAAAGAUCAUGUGUGGGGAGCUACAACACAGAAGACAACAGAGGACCCUGAGGCUCAGCCUCCUUCUACUGAGGAGGAAGGCCUGAUCUUCUGUGAUGCCCCCAGUGCCUAAAUAAUCUGCUCUAGCAACACUCCCUUCAGUCCAGCCAAUCCUGGGUCCUGUGCCACUCCUACAAAUGCUCCAAACUCUGUCCUCAAAUGACUUGUGCCACUCAACCAGGAAAUCUAUCCCAGGUCUAACUCACCUCAGCAGAAGGCACUGUUUUAUGCAAGAAUACCCAUCACAAGAAAAAGGAGUUCAUAGGUUCCUGAACCUCUGCAAUCCCCUGAAAAAGGCUUUCAUUGCCAUUUCCAUUAACAUGCAGGUGAAGCAGGGCAUUCUCCAAAUAUACUUUGUACCUUUAAGCAAA